UGUGCUCGUCGCCGCGCUCGUGGACCGGGGCCGGGCGGACUCGGGGACCGGCGGAGGACGCCGGGCGCGCCCGGCCCGAGGCUGGGGGAGCGGGGCGGCGUGGCGGGCGCGCCGAGGACCCCAGGCCGGGCCGGGCCGAGCAGAGGCUGCCAUGGGCUCCGUGGGGAGCCAGCGCCUUGAGGAGCCCAGCGUGGCAGGCACACCAGACCCGGGCGUAGUGAUGAGCUUCACCUUCGACAGUCACCAGCUGGAGGAGGCGGCGGAGGCGGCUCAGGGCCAGGGCCUUAGGGCCAGGGGCGUCCCAGCUUUCACGGAUACUACAUUGGACGAGCCAGUGCCCGAUGACCGUUAUCACGCCAUCUACUUUGCGAUGCUGCUGGCUGGCGUGGGCUUCCUGCUGCCAUACAACAGCUUCAUCACGGACGUGGACUACCUGCAUCACAAGUACCCAGGGACCUCCAUCGUGUUUGACAUGAGCCUCACCUACAUCUUGGUGGCACUGGCAGCUGUCCUCCUGAACAACGUCCUGGUGGAGAGACUGACCCUGCACACCAGGAUCACCGCAGGCUACCUCUUAGCCUUGGGCCCUCUCCUUUUUAUCAGCAUCUGCGACGUGUGGCUGCAGCUCUUCUCUCGGGACCAGGCCUACGCCAUCAACCUGGCCGCUGUGGGCACCGUGGCCUUCGGCUGCACAGUGCAGCAAUCCAGCUUCUACGGGUACACGGGGAUGCUGCCCAAGCGGUACACGCAGGGGGUGAUGACCGGGGAGAGCACGGCGGGCGUGAUGAUCUCUCUGAGCCGCAUCCUCACGAAGCUGCUGCUGCCCGACGAGCGCGCCAGCACGCUCAUCUUCUUCCUGGUGUCGGUGGCGCUGGAGCUGCUGUGUUUCCUGCUGCACCUGUUAGUGCGGCGCAGCCGCUUCGUGCUCUUCUAUACCACACGGCCGCGUGACAGCCACCGGGGCAGGCCAGGCCUGGGCAGGGGCUAUGGCUACCGCGUGCACCACGACGUUGUCGCCGGGGACGUCCACUUCGAGCACCCAGCCCCGGCCCUGGCCCCCAACGAGUCCCCAAAGGACAGCCCAGCCCACGAGGUGACCGGCAGCGGCGGGGCCUACAUGCGCUUUGAUGUGCCGCGGCCAAGGGUCCAGCGCAGCUGGCCCACCUUCAGAGCCCUGUUACUGCACCGCUACGUGGUGGCGCGGGUGAUCUGGGCCGACAUGCUCUCCAUCGCCGUGACCUACUUCAUCACGCUGUGCCUGUUCCCCGGCCUCGAGUCUGAGAUCCGCCACUGCAUCCUGGGCGAGUGGCUGCCCAUCCUCAUCAUGGCUGUGUUCAACCUGUCAGACUUCGUGGGCAAGAUCCUGGCAGCCCUGCCCGUGGACUGGCGGGGCACCCACCUGCUGGCCUGCUCCUGCCUGCGUGUGGUCUUCAUCCCCCUCUUCAUCCUGUGCGUCUACCCCAGCGGCAUGCCCGCCCUCCGUCACCCCGCCUGGCCCUGCAUCUUCUCACUGCUCAUGGGCAUCAGCAACGGCUACUUCGGCAGCGUGCCCAUGAUCCUGGCGGCAGGCAAAGUGAGCCCCAAGCAGCGGGAGCUGGCAGGGAACACCAUGACCGUGUCCUACAUGUCAGGGCUGACGCUGGGGUCCGCCGUGGCCUACUGCACCUACAGCCUCACCCGCGACGCUCACGGCAGCUGCCUGCACGCCUCCACCGCCAAUGGUUCCAUCCUCGCAGGCCUCUGAGCCAGCCCCGCCCACUGCCAGGGACGCCGAGGGCCUGACCAGGGGCCCCGAGGCCUGAGGGCCCCUCCCCUGUCCCCACCUCAGUGCCUGCGGGGCCCUGAGCCUCCCCCUGUGCCAGCAGCCCCACUCCCUCAGGGUCCAGCCAUGCCCCACCCUGGACUGAAGUUCUGCAAAGUCCUCCGAGGACCGGAACACGUUUCUGCGACCCGGGGCUCUGGCCAGCACUGUGUUCUGCGUUUGGUCUCAUACCUGCGUCUACCUUCCAUCUGUGUCCAGCGGCCCCGGCUCCAGCCCAGCCAGCACUCUGCAGGGUCACACGCACCGUGUCCCCACCCAGGACAGCAGACACCCGCCAGAGUGUGCGCGCCCAGUGACUGCACCCCGGCCCUCAUCACCCACCGGCACUGAUCGGGGCACCGCCUGGCCCAGCCUCCACCAGGGACCCCUCCUCAUGAACUCUGGAGCCCUGAGAGGAGAGGGGCAGCCCCCCACCUUGUCACCCUCAGGGCUUCCCCUUCUGUCCUCAUUCUUAGAGACUGCUUCUCCCAAACAUAACGCGUUAGCCAUGAAGGAGUCGGAGCCCUGGGUCCGAAUGGACCCGCCUGCGGUCUGCAUCAGCCUCUGGGAAACCACAGCAGUGAUGCCAGCUGGGCACGUCAGGACCUCCCCACACACCCACACGAUGCCACAGGUCAGGGGGCUGUGCCUGACUAGGGAGCCCUCCCAUUGCCUUCCUGGCCCGGGAUAGAAGAGGGGAGGUAAGUCUGGGGGCUACGAAGCCGGGCCCCCACACCCUGGCUGAAGUCAGCUUGACCUAGGUCUUGACCCUCAUCCAGCAAGGGACUCGACAGACCCAAGGGUCCCUGGAACGUAGGGAGGGGCUGGGGGUCAGUCCAGCCCGGGCCUCCCAGAACACCAGGCCCGUGUGGGUGGCACCCUGAGGUCAGGGGAUCCUAAGGGUGUCCUUCCAGAGACGGUGUUUCCAGGGGGAGGACCGCCCCCGCUUCCAGAUCCCCGGCCCCGGCUGUGACUGCCCUGUUUCACCCCUGCUGUGUCCCAUCCCCCGUCUGUCCACUAACUGUACCGCACCGGCCAUUAAAAGAUGAAGGCAGACCGCUGCACCGCCGCCUGCAAGCAGAGUUUGUGCGUGGACGGGGGCUGGGACUGCCAUCUCGGGAUACCGGUGGAACUCGGGCUGCCCCGCAUAAGCCGGUCCUCAGUCUUCCCAUCUGUGAGGUGGGCCGGGUGGAUCAGGGAGCAGGAGGGUGUCCUCACACUGGGUAGGCUUGGUUUGUGGGCAGCGCUGGGUAGUGGGGUGAGAGCUGGGAGCACUUAGGGUUUGUCGCUCACCUUGACCGCCCGCCCCCCCCACCCCUUCGUGAGGAUCAGGGAGGAUGGCCACAUGCAGCCCAUUUGAAGGGGAAACAAAGUGGGCGGGGCUUGGCCCCUGCCCCUCAGGGACUGCACUGCAUCCUAGGAGUCAGAGCCUCCUGGCUUCGAGCCUCAUCCCUUUUGCUGAUUUGUGCAAUUUGGACAAAAUCCUGCACUGUUCUGUGCCUCAUUUCUUUCUUUUUUUAUUUUUUUUUUGAGACUGAGUCUUGCUCUUGUCACCCAGGCUGGAGUGCAGUGGCACGAUCUUGGCUCACUGCAAUCUCUGCCUUCCAGGUUCAAGCGAUUCUCCUGCCUCAGCCUCUCAAGUAGCUGGGAUUACAGGUACGCACCACCACACCUGGCUAAUUUGUCUUGUGGAGACCGGGUUUCACCAUGUUGGCCAUGCUGGUCUCGAACUCCUGAUCUCAAGUGAUCCAUCUGUCUCAUCCUCCCAAAGUGUUGGGAUUACAGGUGUGAGCCACUGCACCCGUCCUGUGCCUCAUUUUUGUUUUUUCUUUCUUUACAAGACAGGCUCUCGCUCUGUCACUGAGGCUGGAGUGCAGUGGUGCCAUCAUAGCUCACUGCAGCCUCCACCUCCUGGGCUCCAGUGAUCCUCCCACCUCAGCCUCCCAAAUAGCUGUGAAUACAGGCGCGUGCCACCACGUCUGGCCAGAUUCUUUUAUUUUGUGUAGAGAUGGGGUCUUGCUGUUGCCCAGACUGGUCUCAAAGUCUGGGCCUCAAGUGUUCCCCCUGCCUUGGCCUCCCAAAGUGCCAGGAUUACAGGUAUGAGUCACUGCGCCUGGCCUGUUCUGUCCUUAGCUUCCCCAAGGAAUGGGGCUGGUCCAGGUUUUGAUGUGGGUCCCGUAAAGGAGGGCACGAGGGCCACCUAUGCUCUGGCAGGCAUCCUCCCUGGGGCCCAGGUGGGCGGCCACUUGGGCCAAGACUGCGCCAGGUGACACCAGAGUGUUUCCCAGAGCCCAUGCCGGGCCCUUCCCUUGCCCGAGGCCGGCUGGCUGCCCUCCAUGGGUUACCCUCUUUGCAAAGCCCCGAAUGUCCUCUGCAGGCCACCCACACUAACCAGGUCAGUCACUGGGCAGCCAGACCCCCACCUAUAGCUUCCCUAGGCCCCAGUGCAGAGAUGCCGUCCACCCCCAUCUAGGUGAGGGCUUGGGGCCACUCUUAGCAUUAGUAUCAUUUUCUUCUAGUAUCAUUUUGUGGUAGGCAUGGCUGGAAAUGUGCAGCUUUGCUUUUUUUUUUUUUUUUUUUGGAGGAGUUUCGCUUUUGUUGCCCAGGCUGGAGUGCAAUGGCUCGAUUUCAGCUCACUGCAACCUCUGCCUGCCGGGUUCAAGCGAUUCUCCUGCCUCAGCCUCCCGAGUAGCUGGGAUUACAGGCAUGUGCCACCAUGCCCGGCUAAUUUUGUGCUUUUAGUAGAGACGAGGUUUCUCCAUGUUGGUCAGGCUGGUCUUGAACUCCCGACCUCAGGUGAUCCACCUGCCUCAGCCUCCCAAAGUGCUGGGAUUACAGGCAUGAGCCACCAUGCCUGGCACUGGUUUUUUGAGAUGGAAUCUCGUUAUGUCACCCCAGCUGGAGGGCAGUGGCACGAUCUCAGCUCACUGUAACCUUUGCCGUGGGUUCAAGCGAUUCUCCUGCCUCAGCCUCCCAAGUAGCUGGGAUUACAGGCACGCUCCACCACACCCGGCUAAUUUUUUUGUAUUUUUAGUAGAGAUGGGGUUUCACCAUAUUGGCCAGGCUGGUCUUGAACUCCUGACCUCAAGUGAUCCGCCUCCCUUGGCCUCCCAAAGUGCUGGGAUUACAGGCGUGAGCCACCGUGCCCAUCCAACUUAACUUUUAAUUUUUUCUCAUGUAAAUUUGUUCAAUUUCUUUUUUUUUUUUUUUUUUUUUUUUUGAGACAAUCUCUGUCACCCCCAGGCCAGAGUGCAGUGGUGCGAUCUCAACUCACUGCAACCUCCACCCGCCGGGUCCCUGUGAUUUUCCCACCUCAGCCUCCCGAGUAGCUGGGAUUACAGGUGUGGGCCACCACACCCGGCUAAUUUUUGUAUUUUUAGUAGAGACGGGGUUUCACCACAUUGCUCAGGCUGGUCUGAAACUCCUGGCCUGAAGUGAUCCUCCCGCCUCGGCCUCCUAAAGUGCUGGGAUUACAGGCACGCUCUACCACACCUGGCUAAUUUUUUUUUGUAUUUUUAGUAGAGAUGGGGUUUCACCAUAUUGGCCAGGCUGGUCUCGAACUCCUGACUUCAAGUGAUCCGCCUGCCUUGGCCUCCCAAAGUGCUGGCAUUACAGGCGUGAGCCACUGUGCCCAGCCGAUGAGCUCAUUUAGAUGGCUGCAUGGGGUCACCGCCCCUGCACGCGUGGCACCCAACUUCUUCCAGUCGAAUCCUGCUUCUUGGUGCCCUGAUAUGGCAGAAUGCCCCCAGACACCACCCCUACUCCAGCCCCUGAAAUAAACCACUCCAGACAAUUUUAUUUUUCCAAUUAAAUCUUUUCUUUUUUUUUAUGAAAAAAGAUCACACAGAAUUUGCCAACAAACAAAAUUCCAAAAGAAACAUAAAAAAAAAAACCAAUAAUUCCCCCAAAAAACAAA